AGUGAGCCGAGCAGAGGGGCCGCCUCCGCCCGCACCCAGCAUGCUUCGCCGAGGCUAUAAGGCCUCUGAAAGGCGAAGACACUUGAGCGAGAGGCUCAGCUGGCACCAAGACCAGGCGCUGAGUAGCAGCAUCUACCUCCUACGAGAGAUGGGCCCCACUGGCUUCCUGCUGAGGGAGGAGGAGCCGGAAUACAUGGAUUUCCGAGUUUUUCUAGGAAAUCCUCACGUUUGUAACUGUUCCACAUUUCCGAAAGGAGGGGAACUUUGUAAGCAUAUCUGCUGGGUCUUGUUGAAAAAAUUCAAGCUUCCAAGGAACCAUGAAUCUGCUUUACAACUGGGUCUUGGAGAAAGAGAGAUAAGUGACUUGCUUCGGGGGAUACAUCGAGUUCAAACUCCCCAACCAGGAACAAAUGACGAAAAUGAACAUGUUGAAGAAGAUGGGUACAUUAAACAGAAGGAAAUUGAUUCAGAGGAUAUCUGCUCUAUUUGUCAAGAGCUACUUUUAGAGAAAAAGCUUCCUGUCACCUUUUGCAGGUUUGGCUGUGGCAAUAGUAUUCAUAUAAAAUGCAUGAAGAUCUUAGCUAAUUAUCAGAGUACAUCAAACACUUCCAUGUUGAAAUGUCCUCUGUGCAGGAAAGAGUUUGCACCAUUAAAACUGAUUUUGGAGGAAUUCAAAAACUCUAGCAAACUAGUAGCUGCAGCAGAAAAAGAGAGACUGGACAAACACCUUGGGAUUCCCUGUAAUAACUGCAAACAGUUUCCAAUUGAGGGGAAGUGUUAUAAGUGUACCGAAUGCAUAGAAUAUCACUUAUGCCAGGAAUGUUUUGAUAGCUGCUGCCAUCUUUCCCACACGUUUACAUUUCGUGAGAAAAGAAACCAAAAAUGGAGAUCACUAGAAAAAAGAGCAGAUGAAGUUGUAAAAUACAUAGAUACUAAAAAUGAGAUUGAAGAAAAGAUGUCACAUUUUCAAGAAAAGCAAGGCCAAGUUUACACACCAAAACACAUUGUAAGAUCACUGCCUCUCCAACUGAUUACUAAGAAUAGUAAGCUGCUUGCUCCAGGCUACCAGUGUCUACUUUGUUUGAAGGCAUUUCAUCUUGGUCAACAUACAAGAUUGCUACCAUGUACUCACAAGUUUCACAGGAAGUGUAUUGACAACUGGUUAUUCCACAAGUGCAAUUCAUGCCCUAUUGAUGGACAAGUUAUAUAUAACCCUUUAACUUGGAAAAAUUCAGCAGUGAAUGGACAAGCACAUCAGUCUGUUUCAAACAGAGACAUCAUUCAUCUAUCAAAGCAGAAAGAACCAGAUCUUUUUAUUCCUGGUACUGGAUUAGUCUUAAAACAAAAUAGACUUGGAAUUUUACCUAGCAUACCUCAGUGUAAUUUUGAUGAAUUGAAUACACCUCAAAGCCCAAAAGAUGCCUAUGAAAAUACAACAAUAGAUAAUCUAUGCUCUAUCAAAUUAGAUAAUUCAAAUUCAAAAAAAUUAACCUAUGAUUAUAAAAUUAGCCAACAUUUUCCCAGGUAUCUUCAAGAUUUACCCACUGUGUCAUUUGGGAAAAUACCAUCUCAAACACUGCUUCCUCCUAUUGUUCAUAAGAAUAUUGUGUGUCCCACUGCAAUGGAAAGUCCAUGCAUCAGUGGAAAAUUUCACACUAGUCUAAGCCGGAUGACCAAAGGCUGUAAAUGUAAUAACCACAACCUAAAGAAGACUCCUGCCACUAAAAUAAGAGAGGACAACAAGAGAUCAACUUUACUUCCAGAGGAUUUCAAUCUUAUUGUCAAUUGGAGCACAGCUAAACUUAGUUUGUCUAAAAGGUAUAGUAACUGUAUGGGGGAAAUUACACGAAAAUGUAGUCAUCUAUCAAGACAGCCUGUGUCUCACUCUGUAAAUACAAAAAGUACUGAGCUAUCUUUAAUAAUAGAAGGAGUUCAAUUGUGAAAAAGUUUACUAUCUGAAAAUAUUUGAAUGUUGAAUAUAAAAAAAUGUUUUAUAUAGAACAUAAAAAGCACACAUAGUCUUGACAAAUGUAUAUAAAAUUCUCUGUUGGAAUUUGCCUACUUACCUAUAAACAGCUCACUACACUUAAAGGAAAUGAUUCUAUUACUUAUAUGACUUACAGCAUUAGGUGUCUUCAUGAAUAUAUUCAGGAUGUUAUAAAUAAUGAAUAAUUUUUAGAGCCUUUAUCUUAUUUUACUCUGAUUUUAGAAAUGUUUUACUUAAAUUAAGGAAAUAGAUUUUUCCUACUUUGAGUCACUGUUUUCAAAUAUUUUUCACGGUAGCACAUAACAUGCAGGGAUUACUCCCCGGUACUUCUGUAUUUUUUGCAUUUUUCUUGCACUAGUAAUUACCACAAACCUAUAAAAAAAAACCUUAAAAAACUCCAUAAAGGAGUUUUCUUAUACAUAAAAUGAAAAUAAAAUGAAAUACUAUCAGCUAUGUCACAUUUA